ACUGCUUUCUUGGGAAGAUGGCGGCUGUGUCGGUGUAUGCUCCACCAGUUGGAGGCUUCUCUUUUGAUAACUGCCGCAGGAAUGCCGUCUUGGAAGCCGAUUUUGCAAAGAGGGGAUACAAGCUUCCAAAGGUCCGGAAAACUGGCACGACCAUCGCUGGGGUGGUCUAUAAGGAUGGCAUAGUUCUUGGAGCAGAUACAAGAGCAACUGAAGGGAUGGUUGUUGCUGACAAGAACUGUUCAAAAAUACACUUCAUAUCUCCUAAUAUUUAUUGUUGUGGUGCUGGGACAGCUGCAGACACAGACAUGACAACCCAGCUCAUUUCUUCCAACCUGGAGCUCCACUCCCUCUCCACUGGCCGUCUUCCCAGAGUUGUGACAGCCAAUCGGAUGCUGAAGCAGAUGCUUUUCAGGUAUCAAGGUUACAUUGGUGCAGCCCUAGUUUUAGGGGGAGUAGAUGUUACUGGACCUCACCUCUACAGCAUCUAUCCUCAUGGAUCAACUGAUAAGUUGCCUUAUGUCACCAUGGGUUCUGGCUCCUUGGCAGCAAUGGCUGUAUUUGAAGAUAAGUUUAGGCCAGACAUGGAGGAGGAGGAAGCCAAGAAUCUGGUGAGCGAAGCCAUCGCAGCUGGCAUCUUCAACGACCUGGGCUCCGGAAGCAACAUUGACCUCUGCGUCAUCAGCAAGAACAAGCUGGAUUUUCUCCGCCCAUACACAGUGCCCAACAAGAAGGGGACCAGGCUUGGCCGGUACAGGUGUGAGAAAGGGACUACUGCAGUCCUCACUGAGAAAAUCACUCCUCUGGAGAUUGAGGUGCUGGAAGAAACAGUCCAAACAAUGGACACUUCCUGAAUGGCAUCAGUGGGUGGCUGGCCGCGGUUCUGGAAGGUGGUGAGCAUUGAGGCCCAGUAAGACACUCAUGUGGCUAGUGUUUGCCGAAUGAAACUCAACUCAAUAAAAAACAAAAACCAAAUUGGGCAGCUGA